GCCCCGCUCCCAAGUGCGCGCGGACCCCUAGCUCCCUCUGAGUUGCGCUGGGCUUGGCUGCUGCACCAUGACCCUGGAGGCGAUCCGCUACUCGCGGGGCUCCCUGCAGAUCCUAGACCAGCUGCUGCUGCCCAAGCAGAGCCGCUACGAGGCGGUGGGCUCGGUGCACCAGGCCUGGGAGGCCAUCCGCGCCAUGAAGGUGCGGGGCGCCCCGGCCAUAGCCCUGGUGGGCUGUCUCAGCCUCGCCGUGGAGCUGCAGGCGGGCGCCGGGGGACCGGGACUCGCCGCGCUCGUGGCCUUCGUGCGCGACAAGCUGAGCUUCCUCGUCACCGCCCGGCCCACCGCUGUCAACAUGGCCCGCGCCGCCCGCGACCUGGCUGAUGUUGCAGCCCGGGAGGCCGAACGGGAGGGCGCUACGGAAGAGGCGGUCCGGGAGAGAGUGAUCUGCUGCACCGAGGACAUGCUGGAGAAAGACCUCAGAGACAACCGAAGCAUUGGGGACCUAGGAGCCCGCCACCUCCUGGAGCGGGUGGCCCCCAGCGGUGGCAAGGUGACUGUGCUGACCCACUGUAACACUGGUGCUCUGGCCACCGCUGGCUAUGGUACAGCCCUAGGUGUGAUUCGCUCACUGCACAGCCUGGGCCGCCUGGAGCAUGCCUUCUGCACAGAGACCCGGCCCUACAACCAGGGAGCCCGGCUGACGGCCUUUGAGCUGGUCUAUGAGCAGAUCCCCGCCACCCUUAUCACCGACAGCAUGGUGGCUGCUGCCAUGGCCCAUAGGGGCGUGUCAGCUGUGGUCGUGGGAGCUGACCGCGUGGUUGCCAACGGCGACACAGCCAACAAGGUGGGCACCUACCAGCUGGCCAUUGUCGCCAAGCACCAUGGCAUUCCCUUCUACGUGGCUGCCCCCAGCUCUUCAUGUGACCUCCGUCUGGAGACCGGCAAGGAGAUCAUUAUUGAAGAGCGACCGGGCCAGGAGCUGACCGAUGUUAAUGGGGUCCGGAUUGCAGCACCUGGUUUUCUUAAGAGGAAAUAAGAAUAUCUGGCUGGCCACGUGUUUGUAAAGAAAAACCAAGACGGCCAGGCGAGGUGGCUCACACCUGUAAUCCCAGCACUUUGGGAGGCCGAGGCGGGCAGAUCACAAGGUCAGGAGUUCGAGACCAGCCUGGUCAACAUAGUGAAACCCCGUCUCUACUAAAAAUACAAAAAUUAGCCGGACAUGGUGGCACCCGCCUGUAGUCCCAACUACUCAGGAGGCUGAGGGAGGAGAAUCACUUGAACCUGAGAGGCGGAGGUUGUGGUGAGCUGAGAUUACACCAUUGCACUCCAGCCUGGGCAACAGAGUGAGAUUCUGUCUCAAAAAAAAAAAAGAAAAGAAAAAGCAAGAUAUUUCUACACUUAUUUUUAUUUGUUUAUUUUCAUAGAGAUAGGGUCUCGCUAUGUUCCCCAGGCUGGUCUCAAACUCCUGGCCUCAAGCGAUCCUCCUGCCUCAGCCUCCCAAAGCACUGAGAUUACAGGUGUGAGCUCCCAUGCCUAGCUGCAAGACUUUUCUUAGCUGCCUAUACUUCCUGGCUGUGCAACCGUUAGCAAGUUCCCUAAAUUCUCUAAUUCCCUAAGAUCCUCACUGGUCCUAUCUGUAAAAUGGGCUAUGGCUAGAACCUGCUGCAUAAACCCAAGGGCGGUCAGUGAAUUAACCCACAGGACAUUUAGAUCAAUGACUGGCCCUUUAAAUAGUUCAUGCACUCAGAUGCCGUGGCUCACGCCUAUAAUCCCAACACUUUGGGAGGCGGAGGUGGGCGGAUCACUUGAGGUCAGGCGUUCCAGACCAGCCUAGCCAACAGAGCGAAACCACGUCUCUACUAAAAAAAUAUAAAAAUUAGCCAGGCGUGGUGGCACAUGCCUGUAGUCCCAUCUACUUGGGAAGCUGAGGCAUGAGAAUUGCUUGAACCUAGGACGCAGAGGUUGCAGUAAGUUGAGACUGCACCACUGCACUCCAGUCUGGGUGACAGAGCGAAACUCCAUCUCAAAAAUAAAAAAAAAGGCCGAGCGCUGUGGCUCACGCCUGUAAUCCCAGCACUUUGGGAAGCCGAGGCGGGCGGAUCACCUGAGGUCGGGAGUUCAAGACCAGCCUGACCAACAUGGAGAAACCCUGCCUCUACUAAAAAUACAAAAUUAGCCGGGCGUGGUGGCACAUGCCUGUAACCCCAGCUACUCAGGAGGCUGAGGCAGGAGAAUUGCUUGAACCCGGGAGGCGGAGGUUGCAAUGAGCCAAGAUAGCGCCACAGCACUCCAGCCUGGGCAACAAGAGUGAAACUCCAUCUCAAAGAAAAAAAAGAAAAAACAGUUCAUGAAAUAUUAGCAUGAACCAAUAUUAGCAUUAUGGGGCCAGGUAAAAUGGCUCACACCUGAAAUCCCAGUAUUUUGGGAGGCUGAGGUGGGAGGAUCACUUGAGCUCAGGAGUUCAAGACCAGCCUGGGCAACAUUGCCAGACCACAAUCUCUAAAAAAAUUGUUUUGCCAGGUGUGGUGGUUCAUGAUUGUAACCCCAGCACUUUGGGAGGCUGAGGCGGGCGGAUCACCUGAGGUCAGGGGUUCGAGACCAGCCUGGCCAAUGUGGUGAAACCCCGUCUCUACUAAAAAUACAAAAAAAAAAAACGUUAGCUGGGCGAGGUGGCAGGCGCCUGUAAUCCCAACUACUUGGGAGGCUGAGGCAGGAGAAUCGCUUGAACCUGGGAGGCACAGGUUGCAGUGAGUUGAGAUCAUGUCACUGCACUCCAGCCUAGGUGACAAGAGCAAAACUCCAUCUCAAAAAAACAAAAAAACAGCUAGACAUGAUGGUGCACAUCUGUGGUCCCAGCUGCUCAGGAGGCUGCAGCAGGAGAAUCGUUUGAAUCCAAGAGGCAGAGGUUACACUGAGCCAAGAUCGCACCACUGUACUACAGCCUGGGUGACACAACGAGACUCUGUGUCAAAAAUAAUAAUAAUAAUUAAAAAUAAAACUAAAAAAAUAAGUGGGAUGGGCCAGGUGCGGUGGCUCACGCCUGUAAUCCCAGCACUUUGGGAGGCCGAGGCGGGCAGAUCACCUGAGGUCGGGAGUUUGAGACCAGCCUGACCAACAUGGAAAAACCUCGUCUCUACUAAAAAUACUGGCUGGGCAUGGUGGUGCAUGCCUGUAAUCCCAGCUACUCGGGAGGCUGAGGCAGGAGAAUUGCUUGAAACCUGGGAGGUGGAGGUUGCAGUGAACCAAGAUCGUGCCAUUGCACUCCAGCCUGGGCAACAAGAGCAAAACUACAUCUCACAAAAAAUAAAAAAAUAAGUGGCA